AUCGCCGGGAGGGCGGUUGAGGCGGUGGUGGCGGCGUCGGCGGCGGCCGGGCGCUGGCUGAGGGGCGCUGAGGCGGGAGCUGUGGCGGCGCUGGGCGCCCCUGGCUCCUCGGCCUCUGCCGGCCAUGGGCUCCGAGAAGGACUCCGAGUCGCCGCGCUCCACAUCGCUACAUGCGGCCGCACCCGACCCUAAGUGCCGCAGCGGCGGCCGGCGCCGGCGCCUCACCUUGCACAGCGUCUUCUCUGCCUCGGCCCGCGGCCGCCGCGCCCGGGCCAAGCCGCAGGCCGAGCCGCCGCCCCCGGCUGCGCAGCCGCCGCCCGCCCCGGCCCCUGCCGCGGCCCAGGGCCCGCCGCCCGAGGCGCUGCCCGCCGAGCCGGCCGCCGAGGCCGAGGCGGAGGCCGCGGCGGCGGCGGCGGAGCCUGGGUUCGACGAUGAGGAGGCGGCGGAGGGCGGUGGCCCGGGCGCGGAGGAGGUGGAGUGUCCGCUGUGCCUGGUGCGGCUGCCGCCUGAGCGGGCCCCGCGCCUCCUCAGCUGUCCGCACCGCUCGUGCCGGGACUGCCUCCGCCACUACCUGCGCCUGGAGAUAAGCGAGAGCAGGGUGCCCAUCAGCUGCCCCGAGUGCAGCGAGCGACUCAACCCGCACGACAUCCGCUUGCUGCUCGCCGACCCGCCGCUUAUGCACAAGUACGAGGAGUUCAUGCUGCGCCGCUACCUAGCCUCGGACCCCGACUGCCGCUGGUGCCCGGCCCCGGACUGCGGUUAUGCUGUUAUUGCCUAUGGCUGUGCCAGCUGCCCGAAGCUAACUUGUGAGAGGGAAGGUUGCCAGACUGAGUUCUGCUACCACUGCAAGCAGAUAUGGCAUCCAAAUCAGACAUGCGAUAUGGCCCGUCAACAGAGGGCCCAGACUUUACGAGUUCGGACCAAACACACUUCAGGUCUCAGUUAUGGGCAAGAAUCUGGACCAGCAGAUGACAUCAAGCCAUGCCCACGAUGCAGUGCAUACAUUAUCAAGAUGAAUGAUGGAAGCUGUAAUCACAUGACCUGUGCAGUGUGUGGCUGUGAAUUCUGUUGGCUUUGUAUGAAAGAGAUCUCAGACUUGCAUUACCUCAGCCCCUCUGGCUGUACAUUCUGGGGCAAGAAGCCAUGGAGCCGUAAGAAGAAAAUUCUUUGGCAGCUGGGCACGUUGAUUGGUGCUCCAGUGGGGAUUUCUCUCAUUGCUGGCAUUGCCAUUCCUGCCAUGGUCAUUGGCAUUCCUGUUUAUGUUGGAAGGAAGAUUCACAGCAGGUAUGAGGGAAGGAAAACCUCCAAACACAAGAGGAAUUUGGCUAUCACUGGAGGAGUGACUUUGUCGGUCAUUGCAUCCCCAGUUAUUGCUGCAGUUAGUGUUGGUAUUGGUGUCCCCAUUAUGCUGGCAUAUGUUUAUGGGGUUGUGCCCAUUUCUCUUUGUCGUGGAGGCGGCUGUGGAGUUAGCACAGCCAACGGAAAAGGAGUGAAAAUUGAAUUUGAUGAAGAUGAUGGUCCAAUCACAGUGGCAGAUGCCUGGAGAGCCCUCAAGAAUCCCAGCAUUGGGGAAAGCAGCAUUGAAGGCCUGACUAGUGUAUUGAGCACUAGUGGAAGCCCUACAGAUGGACUUAGUGUUAUGCAAGGUCCUUACAGCGAAACGGCCAGCUUUGCAGCCCUCUCAGGGGGCACGCUGAGUGGCGGCAUUCUCUCCAGUGGCAAGGGAAAAUAUAGCAGGUUAGAAGUUCAAGCCGAUGUCCAAAAGGAAAUUUUCCCCAAAGACACAGCCAGUCUUGGUGCAAUUAGUGACAACGCAAGCACUCGUGCUAUGGCCGGUUCCAUAAUCAGUUCCUACAACCCACAGGACAGAGAAUGCAACAAUAUGGAAAUCCAAGUGGACAUUGAAGCCAAACCAAGCCACUAUCAGCUGGUGAGUGGAAGCAGCACGGAGGACUCGCUCCAUGUUCAUGCUCAGAUGGCAGAGAAUGAAGAAGAAGGUAGUGGUGGCGGAGGCAGUGAAGAGGAUCCCCCCUGCAGACACCAAAGCUGUGAACAGAAAGACUGCCUGGCCAGCAAACCUUGGGACAUCAGCCUGGCCCAGCCUGAAAGCAUCCGCAGUGACCUAGAGAGUUCUGAUGCACAGUCAGACGAUGUGCCAGACAUCACCUCAGAUGAGUGUGGCUCCCCCCGCUCCCAUACUGCAGCCUGCCCCUCGACCCCCAGAGCCCAAGGUGCACCGAGCCCAAGUGCCCAUAUGAACCUCUCUGCCCUAGCCGAGGGACAAACUGUCUUGAAGCCAGAAGGUGGAGAAGCCAGAGUAUGAAGUGGAAUGAAUGCUCCUGUUCUGAGAAGCACACUUAUGCACUUUUGUCUUCCUGGCCAGUGUUUUACUACAAUGAGGAUGGCAAGUCUGGACAACAGCCAGCUUAGAAGAUUCUUAUCUCUUGGGCACUGCAGCCAGACUUCACACAUUUCCCUGCACCUAGGACAGGAAAUGCUGUUAGUGGACUUUGGAUUUCUGGAAGAAUGUUCCCUGAAGGGGGCGUGUACUUGUGUGAAAAAGAGAACUUGUUGGAAAAAGAGGCAGACAGCCUGGAGAUCUCUGAAACGCAAAUUAUCAACUCAAAACUUGGAAUUCUCUUGAAGCCUCGAGAGAACAAUUCACUUCUUUGAUAAAAUCAAAGAAGUCUGUUGGAGGGGCAGUAGUUUAUGGCUAAACCUAUAUUUCUUAUCUGGGUUCCACUUACUACAGCUGUGAGAUUUGGGCAGUUUACUCUGAGUCUGUUUUCACUUAGCCAAAAUGGAGAUGAUGAUCCUAGUUAAGGGGUUGUGAAGACUGAGAUGGUAUACUGAAAAUGUUUUUGGUAAAGGCCCAUGUUUUUUCCUCCUGCAGGAAGAAGAAGAAAUGAGUUAAAGGAGAUUUUAGAUAUCAUAUAAGAAAGGAAGCCUAGACCUCUAGGCCAGAGGCUAUGAAAAAUUUAAAUUUAUUCUAAUCCUUAGCGACACUUUAGUAGAUGAAAAGGCCCAUCAUCACCACCUAGAGGCGAACACAAAUAAUGCAUUAGAAAAGUUACAAUAGCUUGGCCGGGCGUGGUGGCUCAUGCCUGUAAUCCCAGCACUUUGGGAGGCUGAGGCGGGCGGCUCACAAGGUCGGGAGAUCGAGACCAUCCUGGCUAACACGGGUGAAACCCCGUCUCUACUAAAAAUACACAAAAUUAGCCGGGCGUAGUGGUGGGCGCCUGUAGUCCCAGCAACUCGAGAGGCUGAGGCAGGAGAAUGGCGUGAACCCGGGAGGCAAAGCUUGCAGUGAGCUGAGAUUGCGCCACUGCACUCCAGCCUGGGCAACAGAGCGAGACUCCGUCUCACAAAAAAAAAAAAAUAAUAAUAAUAGCUUAGAAAAUGGAGAAAGUUUAAUUUCCUCUUCAUACAGCCUUCAUUCAUUCUGAAAUACCUACCGCAUUUCAGGUAUAAGAUGUAGCAAUGACUAAAAUACAAAGUUCCUGUCCCCAUGGAACUUAGACUCUUAACGGGGGAAGGCAAUCAGAUAUAUAACCUGGAGUGAGGAUAAGUAAUCUGUGAAGAAAAACAGGGAAGACAGAGUGGUAGAUAGUGCUACUUGACAUGACCAGGUUGGUCCUCCUUGAUAAGGUUCCAUUUUAUUAGAGACUUUAAUGGAGCAAGGAAGAGAACUAUGUGAAUAUCUAGGGGAAGCACAUACCAGACAUGAGGAAUAAACUACAAAGGCCCUUUGGUAGAGCAUCCUUAGUCUGUUUCCAAAAAAGCAUAGUAUAGAGGCCUAUAUGGCUGGAACAAAGUGGACCAAGGUGGGGAGAGUAGUGGAUUAGGUCAAAGACAGCUGGAGCAAGAUUGUGUAGAUUAGCCAAACAACUCUGAAGACAAGGAAAUUUUAGAUUUCUUUGGGCCAGGAGGAGGUAAUCUUCAGCGCCAGACAGAUGCAGUGCUUGCGGCCAGCUUUCAAAAAGGUUGAAACUGGGAGGGGCAUGUCUGAUCACUAGUACUACUUGGACAGGCCAAUGUGAAGAAGCUUGUGGAUAUGGUAAAUGAAUACUCAUUUAUGCUCACCUAAUGUACCUUCGUAUGCUGCAGAGGCUGGAAAACUAAAAACUUCAUGUCUUAGAUUUCCUUGAAACCAAGGUUCUGAAUGUAACCUAAGGUCAAGUUUUGCCAGUUAGAUGCACAAACAAGAUGUGGAAGGAGGAGUGAUUCAGGGGUUAUCUUUAGCUACUUUGGCUAUUGCUCCUGCAAGAUGUAGAGACCUUAGGUUUCUCUUUAACUGCAUUCUAAUAGCCAUCAGUAGCUUUGUGGGUGUUGAAGGGUGUCUGGAUCCAUAGAUAGCAGUUUGCGAUAUGUUUUCUUGUAGUCAACCUGUAGUGGCCUCCUAAUUGCUCAUCUCCCCUAUGGUGGCAGAGGUAGCAGCUCACAUGGAAGGCUAAUUCCAGGUCUGGGAAUCGCCUGGAGGCCCAGCCUAUGGCCAUGUUCCCCAGGCUUUCCAGUGCUUUUGUAAGCACCUAAUUUACCUGUGUUGAAUCCUUUUCCACUUAAAAUUGGUAGAGGAGUAUUGUUUCCUGCAGUUACUGAAUCCUGGCUAAUAUAGUAUUUGGUUCCAAAAGUGGUUACUAGUAACAGGCCCUCAAAGAUGGGCUUCUUAGAUUAGUUAUGACUAAGCUGCAUUUGAAUGAAAUGUAGAUCUAGUCACCAUUGGAAAAUGAUAAACUGGUAGGCAAAUUGCUUACACCUGUGGUCACCUGAAAUGAAAUGUCUUUUGGAGAAAAGACGUUGGCACCUCAAAGGGCUGCCAUGAUAGAUCAUCAUGUAAGAAAUGGGGACAAAUGAUGGUGACUACACUAGAGGGGUUAAAGGAAAAAGACAAAAAGCUCAAAAGUUUGACAUUUGCAGCUCAAGGCAUAGUAUGGGAGAGACCCAAAAGAAUUUUAUCUUUUGUAGCCGCAAGGCUCAUGUACAUCAAAAUCAAAGGGAGAUUCUGGAUCACUGAAUUACAUACAACAUAAGUUGAAUUCGUAGCUUUACCAGGCCUCUUAUGUGAAAAUGGGGCUCUGAAAUGAGCAAUGGGGACCCUUGAGUGGAUUUGGAUAAAUCCUAGUGCUGUCAACUCACAAACUCUACUUCUUUUAACCAGCAGAAGCAGCCAUUCUUCCCCUUAUAGAUAUGGCUGGUUCUGCUGCUUGAAGACCCUGGGGUAGUUGUCUUAAAGGGGAAUACUAAUACUUCUCGUGUCCCACCCCCUACCCCUCCUUGCUACCAGCUCUAACUAGAGUCAGAUCCCAGUAUGCUUCUGGAAGGCAAACCCAAAGUCUGAUCUGAGAGACUUACAGAAGAAUUGUAAGACUUUGCUAAUUUGUAUCAGCAGAAACAAGGGGAAAAUGUGUAGAGUAUAUUCCAAAGAUGUUGGACCAGGAAGAUAGGAAUAUACAUUUAUUUUCAUUUGCAUUGAAUUUAUCAAUAUGGGGGUACUAGAGGUUCUGGACUCAGCAUAUUGGCUUUAGCAGCUAAGAAUUUUUUUUUUUUUGGAGACAGAGUCUUGCUCUGUUGCCUACGCUGGAGUGCAGAGGCGCAAUCUCGGCUCACUGCAACCUCUGCUUCCCAGGUUCAAGCAAUCCUCCCACCUCAGCCUCCCAAGUAGCUGGAAUUACAGGCUCAUGCCAGCACACCUGGCUACUUUUUGUAUUUUUACUAGAGGUGGGGUUUCACCAUGUUGGCCAGGCUGGUCUUGAACUCCCGACCUCAAGUGAUCUGCCCACCUUGGCCUCCCAAAGUGCUGGGAUUACAGGCGUGAGCCACUGCGACCGGCCAAGAAUGGCUCUUAACAGGUUGUUGGAUGAAACCUGGACUUAAAAGUGGCCUAUACAGAGAUGGCAAAAAUUCCUUAGUGUAGAAUUAGAAGAAUCAAGGCCAGGUGUUGUGGCUGAUGCUUGUAAUCCCAGCACUCUGGGAGGCUGAGGUGGGAGGACUGCUUGAGGCCAGGAGUUUGAAACUAGCCUGGGCAAUAUAGUGAGACCCCAUCUCUACAAAAAGUUAAAAAAUUAGCUGGGCAUGGUGGUGUGUGCCUGUAUAGUUCCAGCUACUCAGGAGGCUGAAGUGGGAGGAUUCCUUGAACUCAGGGAUUUGAGGCUGCAGUGAACUAUGAUCGUGCCACUGCACUCCAGCCUGGGCAACAGAGCUAGACCCCAUCUCAAAAAAAAAAAAUCAGCCGGGCAUGGUGGCUCAUACCUGUAAUCCCGGAACAUUGGGAGGCCGAGGCGGAUGGAUCACUUGAGGCCAGGAGUUCCAGACCAGCCUGGCCAAUAUGGUGAAGCCCUGUCUCUACUAAAAAUACAAAAACUAGCUGGGCAUGGUGGUGUGCAUCUGUAGUCCCAGCUACUCAGAAGGCUGAGGCAUGAGAAUCUCUUGAACCCAGGAGGCAGAGGUUGCAGUGAGCUGAGAUCAUGCCACUGCACUCCAGCCUGGGUGACAGAGCAAGACUCUGUCUCAAAUAAUAACUUAAAAACAUGAUACUAAAAACAUUGAUUUGUAGAUUUAUCAUAUGUGUGACCUACUUACCUCCUAAUUUUGCCCUUCAAAAUUGCCAAGAGGUUAUUUCUUUCAGCAAGGAAUUGAAAAGUACUUUAAACAAGGGAAACACCUUAUCUUGAAAAGUUUGUAGUGUGUACCUUCCCUAGGCUGGAAAUGAAGCUAAGAGAUGUUACCAUUGUAAAGGAAUCCCUGAUAUCAGUAGAGAUGAUGGGAUCCUGCAGUGCCAGUGGCCAAGGGGUAGUACCAAGGCAACAGAGCUGUAGUGAUGAAAUACAUGGGUUACCUACCAAGGUUCUAUUUGGCUUAUAGAACGCAAAACAAAUCUUCAGGUCUGGCAAAUAGAGGCCUGUUUUGAGUCACCAAAAUGGAGAUUUACAGACAAUUCUCAGAGCUGAAGCCCUUGAAAAAGGGGGUGCAGGGUACUCUGGAGGAAGCACCCAGCAAUACCACCAUAACUAUAUCAUAAAUCUUCUCGUUUUCCCCAAAGGGAUCUUAAGCCAUGUAACUAUGCAUGUGUGCUUAGGGAAAUGGAAAUGCCCAGGCCUUUAGGGAUUACUUGGAAACUGGCCCUAAGCCAGCACAAAUGCUGAGACCUAAAAAGCCUUUGUGGUCCACUAGUUAGAAUAGAGGCUUCCAUGGUGUUAUGGGUCGAAUUGUGUCCCUUCCACCAAAAAUCAUAUGUUGAAGUCCUAGCCCCUAGUACCUCAAAAUGUGCCCUUAUUUGGAAAAUGAGGUUGUUGCAGAUAUAAUUAAGAUGAGGUCUUAUUGGCAUAGGGUGGCCCCCUAAUUCGAUUGUUGUACAUAUAAAAAGGGGAAAUCUGAACACAAAGACAUGCACAUAGGCUAAGUACCAUGUGAAGAUGAAGGCAGAGACUGGGGUGAUGCAGCAGAGGCCAAGGGACACCAAGGAUUGCCAGCAAACCAUCAGAAGCUGGGAGCGGCAAGGAACAGAUCCUCCCCCACAGCCCGCGGAAGGAACCAAUUCUGCCAAAAUCUAGGACUUCUAGCUUCCUGAACUGUGAGACAAUAAAUUUCUGUUACUUAAGUCA